CCCAAAGCUCAAUUUCAUUUAGACCCUGCAGCCAAAUUUCACAGACACACCAGAACCCCUUCCGGUCUCCUUGCCCUCUGACUGCAUCCUCUGGUGAUACUGAGCUCUGGAAGGAACUCGUAGAAAGAAUUUGUCUGGUGGAACAGAAGACUUCCCAAGGCAUCUAAGCGUCAGCCCUCCCCUGCACACUCUCUCCCACCUCCUCCCCUUCCUCUCCUGAUUUCUAAGCACAUACUCAGGGAGACAGACGAUGCUCACCCAGUCAGUAAGAAGAGUCCAGCCUGGGAAGAAGAACCCCAGCAUCUUUGCCAAGCCUGCCGACACCCUGGAGAGCCCUGGUGAGUGGACAACAUGGUUCAACAUCGACUACCCAGGCGGGAAGGGCGACUAUGAGCGGCUGGACGCCAUUCGCUUCUACUAUGGGGACCGUGUAUGUGCCCGUCCCCUGCGGCUAGAGGCUCGGACCACUGACUGGACACCUGCGGGCAGCACUGGCCAGGUGGUCCAUGGUAGUCCCCGUGAGGGUUUCUGGUGCCUCAACAGGGAGCAGCGGCCUGGCCAGAACUGCUCUAAUUACACCGUACGCUUCCUCUGCCCACCAGGAUCCCUGCGCCGAGACACAGAGCGCAUCUGGAGCCCAUGGUCUCCCUGGAGCAAGUGCUCAGCUGCCUGUGGUCAGACUGGGGUCCAGACUCGCACACGCAUUUGCUUGGCAGAGAUGGUGUCGCUGUGCAGUGAGGCCAGCGAAGAGGGUCAGCACUGCAUGGGCCAGGACUGUACAGCCUGUGACCUGACCUGCCCAAUGGGCCAGGUGAAUGCUGACUGUGAUGCCUGCAUGUGCCAGGACUUCAUGCUUCAUGGGGCUGUCUCCCUUCCCGGAGGUGCCCCAGCCUCAGGGGCUGCUAUCUACCUCCUGACCAAGACGCCGAAGCUGCUGACCCAGACAGACAGUGAUGGGAGAUUCCGAAUCCCUGGCUUGUGCCCUGAUGGCAAAAGCAUCCUGAAGAUCACAAAGGUCAAGUUUGCCCCCAUUGUACUCACAAUGCCCAAGACUAGCCUGAAGGCAGCCACCAUCAAGGCAGAGUUUGUGAGGGCAGAGACUCCAUACAUGGUGAUGAACCCUGAGACAAAAGCACGGAGAGCUGGGCAGAGCGUGUCUCUGUGCUGUAAGGCCACAGGGAAGCCCAGGCCAGACAAGUAUUUUUGGUAUCAUAAUGACACAUUGCUGGAUCCUUCCCUCUACAAGCAUGAGAGCAAGCUGGUGCUGAGGAAACUGCAGCAGCACCAGGCUGGGGAGUACUUUUGCAAGGCCCAGAGUGAUGCUGGGGCUGUGAAGUCCAAGGUUGCCCAGCUGAUUGUCAUAGCAUCUGAUGAGACUCCUUGCAACCCAGUUCCUGAGAGCUAUCUUAUCCGGCUGCCCCAUGAUUGCUUUCAGAAUGCCACCAACUCCUUCUACUAUGACGUGGGACGCUGCCCUGUUAAGACUUGUGCAGGGCAGCAGGAUAAUGGGAUCAGGUGCCGUGAUGCUGUGCAGAACUGCUGUGGCAUCUCCAAGACAGAGGAAAGGGAGAUCCAGUGCAGUGGCUACACGCUACCCACCAAGGUGGCCAAGGAGUGCAGCUGCCAGCGGUGUACGGAAACUCGGAGCAUCGUGCGGGGCCGUGUCAGUGCUGCUGACAAUGGGGAGCCCAUGCGCUUUGGCCAUGUGUACAUGGGGAACAGCCGUGUAAGCAUGACUGGCUACAAGGGCACUUUCACCCUCCAUGUCCCCCAGGACACUGAGAGGCUGGUGCUCACAUUUGUGGACAGGCUGCAGAAGUUUGUCAACACCACCAAAGUGCUACCUUUCAACAAGAAGGGGAGUGCCGUGUUCCAUGAAAUCAAGAUGCUUCGUCGGAAAAAGCCCAUCACUUUGGAAGCCAUGGAGACCAACAUCAUCCCCCUGGGGGAAGUGGUUGGUGAAGACCCCAUGGCUGAACUGGAGAUUCCAUCCAGGAGUUUCUACAGGCAGAAUGGGGAGCCCUACAUAGGAAAAGUGAAGGCCAGUGUGACCUUCCUGGAUCCCCGGAAUAUUUCCACAGCCACAGCUGCCCAGACUGACCUGAACUUCAUCAAUGACGAAGGAGACACUUUCCCCCUUCGGACGUAUGGCAUGUUCUCUGUGGACUUCAGAGAUGAGGUCACCUCAGAGCCACUUAAUGCUGGCAAAGUGAAGGUCCACCUUGACUCGACCCAGGUCAAGAUGCCAGAGCACAUAUCCACAGUGAAACUCUGGUCACUCAAUCCAGACACAGGGCUGUGGGAGGAGGAAGGUGAUUUCAAAUUUGAAAAUCAAAGGAGGAACAAAAGAGAAGACAGAACCUUCCUGGUGGGCAACCUGGAGAUUCGUGAGAGGAGGCUCUUUAACCUGGAUGUUCCUGAAAGCAGGCGGUGCUUUGUUAAGGUGAGGGCCUACCGGAGUGAGAGGUUCUUGCCUAGUGAGCAGAUCCAGGGGGUUGUGAUCUCCGUGAUUAACCUGGAGCCUAGAACUGGCUUCUUGUCCAACCCUAGGGCCUGGGGCCGCUUUGACAGUGUCAUCACAGGCCCCAACGGGGCCUGUGUGCCUGCCUUCUGUGAUGACCAGUCCCCUGAUGCCUACUCUGCCUAUGUCUUGGCAAGCCUGGCUGGGGAGGAACUGCAAGCAGUGGAGUCUUCUCCUAAAUUCAACCCAAAUGCAAUUGGCGUCCCUCAGCCCUAUCUCAACAAGCUCAACUACCGUCGGACGGACCAUGAGGAUCCACGGGUUAAAAAGACAGCUUUCCAGAUUAGCAUGGCCAAGCCAAGGCCCAACUCAGCUGAGGAGAGCAAUGGGCCCAUCUAUGCCUUUGAGAACCUCCGGGCAUGUGAAGAGGCACCACCCAGUGCAGCCCACUUCCGGUUCUACCAGAUUGAGGGGGAUCGAUAUGACUACAACACAGUCCCCUUCAACGAAGAUGACCCUAUGAGCUGGACUGAAGACUAUCUGGCAUGGUGGCCAAAGCCGAUGGAAUUCAGGGCCUGCUAUAUCAAGGUGAAGAUUGUGGGGCCACUGGAAGUGAAUGUGCGAUCCCGCAACAUGGGGGGCACUCAUCGGCAGACAGUGGGGAAGCUGUAUGGAAUCCGAGAUGUGAGGAGCACUCGGGACAGGGACCAGCCCAAUGUCUCAGCUGCCUGUCUGGAGUUCAAGUGCAGUGGGAUGCUCUAUGAUCAGGACCGUGUGGACCGCACCCUGGUGAAGGUCAUCCCCCAGGGCAGCUGCCGUCGAGCCAGUGUGAACCCCAUGCUGCAUGAGUACCUGGUCAACCACUUGCCACUUGCAGUCAACAACGACACCAGUGAGUACACCAUGCUGGCACCCUUGGACCCACUGGGCCACAACUAUGGCAUCUACACUGUCACUGACCAGGACCCUCGCACGGCCAAGGAGAUCGCGCUCGGCCGGUGCUUUGAUGGCACAUCCGAUGGCUCCUCCAGAAUCAUGAAGAGCAAUGUGGGAGUAGCCCUCACCUUCAACUGUGUAGAGAGGCAAGUAGGCCGCCAGAGUGCCUUCCAGUACCUCCAAAGCACCCCAGCCCAGUCCCCUGCUGCAGGCACUGUCCAAGGAAGAGUGCCCUCGAGGAGGCAGCAGCGAGCGAGCAGGGGUGGCCAGCGCCAGGGUGGAGUGGUGGCCUCUCUGAGAUUUCCUAGAGUUGCUCAACAGCCCCUGAUCAACUAAGUUUUGUGGUACUUCACCCUCUUCUGCCCUCAUUUCAUGUGACAGCCAUUGUGAGACUGAUGCACAAACUGUCACUUGGUUAAUUUAAGCACUUCUGUUUUCGUGAAUUUGCUUGUUUGUUUCUUCAUGCCUUUACUUACUUUGUCCCAUGCUACUGAUUGGCACGUGGCCCCCACAAUGGCACAAUAAAGCCCCUUUGUGAAACUGUUCUUUAAAUGAAACACAAGAAAUUGGCCACUGGUAAAACUCUGCAGCUUCAACUGUACUUCAUUUAAUGCCAUUAAUGCAAAUAUACUUCCUCUUCUUUUUGCAUGGUUUUGCCCACCUCUGCAAUAGUGAUAAUCUGAUGCUGAAGAUCAAAUAACCAAUAUAAAGCAUAUUUCUUGGCCUUGCUCCACAGGACAUAGGCAAGCCUUGAUCAUAGUUCAUACAUAUAAAUGGUGGUGAAAUAAAGAAAUAAAACACAAUACUUUUACUUGAAAUGUAAAUAACUUAUUUAUUUCUUUGCUAAAUUUGGAAUUCUAGUGCACAUUCAAAGUUAAGCUAUUAAAUAUAGGGUGAUCAUAGUUCCUCUACCAAGUCUGGAAAGAACAUCUCCUGGUAUCCACAAUUACACCAGGUUGCUAACUGUAUUUGUACAUUUCCCUUUGCAUUCGCUUCUGUUCUUGCUAGAAACCCAGUGUAGCCCAGGGCAGAUGUCAAUAAAUGCAUACUCUGUAUUUCGAUUCUGAGGCCACUGUCCUGUCUUAACUAUUAAAGUGAGCCAGCUUCUCAGAGGAGUACAGGGGACUCUGGAAAGCAGUCACAGGUGGUGUAAGUCCUCGCCCCCUAAGUUACAGGGCAGGGCAACAUAGGCACACACUCCAGCAGUCAAAUUUGUUCUCAUGGAUCACAUUUUCCGUUUGCAGAAAAGAGCAGAUUCCUGGAGUUGUGAGCAUGUUCUGGGCUCCUGAGCAAGACUAAAAACACGUCCCGAUUUUUUUCUUUCCUUCUUUCCAAUACUUUGGAGCUUAUACAAUGGCUUGGCCCAGGGUCUGACAAGCUGGCCAAGUGGUCCUUUGGCUCUCCCAACAGCCUGUUGCCUUCUCCAGCUGGGCUGGCCGGCCUCACUCAGAAAUGGGCUUUUACUUUUUUCUUUAUGCUCUUCUAAAGAUGUUCAACUUUUCCAGACACCAGAUCUCUGUUGUGUGUUACAGACCCUGUCCCUGGAGCAAAACAAUUGGUCCAAACGGGCAGAGUUUUGGUUUUGGAAAAGGUAUUUGGUUUAAAAUAGUAAAUCAGAGGCCCAUAGGUGGUGCCAGAGCGAUCUCAGCGGCAUUACAGUCAGGGUAGUGGGGUGUGGGGUUGGAUAGGAUGCACUCACUGCCCCUAUCCCAACCCCUCCAGAAUCUGUCAGGCAAGAGUCCAAAGGGUUUGGGAGAAGAGAGGACACUGUUUACAAUCAGGACAAAAAGCUUUCCCUGAUGCCCUGGCCAGCCUAGUGCAGCUCCUUUACCCAUCUCUGGCCUGGGCUGGAUUUGUACUCUUGGAUCACCAUCUGCCCGGCUCCUGGGAAUUUGGUUUGUAAGCAAUUAGAAAUUUCUCUAGCUGAGCACAUCACAAUAACCAUAGAAAAAGCAAGCAUCUGCAGGAGUGAGGACUAGUGGUCUUGUGAUUGCAACUUGACCCACUUCCAGACUCCACAUCUGUCCCACUGCUCCCAGGAAGCAGCUCUCACUGACUGCUUGGGGAGGCUUGACUGCCCCUGUUGUGAGUGCACAGCUAUCUGCAGCACCAUCGCCCCAGCCACUUCAGGAGCCAGAGUGCCUGCUGCUUCAACCUGACCACCAGUUCACUUCAAACUCACGGGGGGAGGGGGAGGGUCGGGGGGGGGUGGGUUGCUGGGGAAGGUGGGCUGACUGGUUCCCCACUCUAGGGCACUUUCCUUGCUGUUCUCAAUUGAGGGCCUGAAUAAAUGGACUCCAGCACACA